ACGGUUCCGCGGGUCCACGCCAGGGGGCAGAAGAGGCGCUGGUCGGCGCUUCUCCUUUCUUUGCCGAGUGCGAGGAGUUGGUCUGAAGCAGGAGUCGAUCUUCCAGUUGUGUGCAAGUGCAUAUACGUGUAGCCUAGUAGCCCGUGUCCUUGUUCCUUGAGACCGCGCUGCCUCCGCCACGUGUCACACGCCCAGGCACACGUCCCCGUAGGGAGAGCCGGGGGAGCCUGCGCGGUCCCUUGGAUCGGUCCGCUCGGCACAGCAGUACGGGGAAGACGGUCUGAGCCAGAACCGACCCAGGGCUCGCGAGUUGGCCCACAAUUCCCAGUCUGCAUUCGAGCACUGAGCUGCGACCUGCGGGCUGGCCUUCCUAAGGACGAUGCUCCUGAAUGGACGCCUGGAGUCCCACGGGUGACACCAUGAAAUAUAUCAAGUUCAGUUCUUACCUGUAGUUGUCUAACGAGGAAUGCACACAUUCGCAAGCUGUGGAACCCUACUAAUAUUGGAUCCAGAUGAAGCUGGGCUAAGGCUUUUUAGAAGCUUUGACUGGAAUGAUGGUUUGUUUGAUGUGACUUGGAGUGAGAACAACGAACAUGUCCUCAUCACCUGUAGUGGCGAUGGCUCGCUGCAGCUCUGGGACACUGCCAAAGCUGCAGGGCCACUGCAAGUCUAUAAAGAACACGCUCAGGAGGUGUAUAGUGUUGAUUGGAGCCAAACCAGAGGUGAACAGCUUGUGGUGUCUGGCUCAUGGGAUCAAACUGUCAAAUUGUGGGAUCCAACUGUUGGAAAGUCUCUGUGCACCUUUAGAGGCCAUGAAAGUAUUAUUUAUAGCACAAUCUGGUCUCCCCACAUCCCUGGUUGUUUUGCUUCAGCCUCAGGUGAUCAGACUCUGAGAAUAUGGGAUGUGAAGGCAGCAGGAGUAAGAAUCGUGAUUCCUGCACAUCAGGCAGAAAUCUUGAGUUGUGACUGGUGUAAAUACAAUGAGAAUUUGCUGGUGACCGGGGCGGUUGACUGUAGUUUGAGAGGCUGGGACUUAAGGAAUGUACGACAACCAGUGUUUGAACUUCUUGGUCAUACCUAUGCUAUUAGGAGGGUGAAAUUUUCACCAUUUCAUGCUUCUGUGCUGGCCUCUUGCUCGUAUGAUUUUACUGUAAGAUUCUGGAACUUUUCAAAGCCUGACUCUCUUCUUGAAACAGUGGAGCAUCAUACAGAGUUUACUUGUGGUUUAGACUUCAGUCUUCAGAGCCCCACUCAGGUGGCUGACUGUUCUUGGGAUGAAACAAUAAAGAUCUAUGACCCUGCUUGUCUUACUAUUCCUGCUUGAGAUACACUACUUUGGUCAGAAACAGAGGAUGUUGGCUGAAGAACUGCCUAACAGCAAAUAAAUUAACUAUGGAAAACAUAGACAUUAUGCUUUUAUAUGCUAUUCAGAUUUCAAAUCUUUCCAAUUUACCCUGGAAUCAGUUUUGAGGGAGCUGAUAAAGACUUUAGCUGACUCGUUAAGCCUGAUACAUAAGCCAUAUUUAAAAUUCUAAGAAAUAAUUAAUGUUAUGAUAUAUCUUGUAGUAUCUAUUAAAAUGUCUCUGGGUCAUAAAAUGGAUUAAAAUAUGGGAGAUCAGUAGGUUAUACUUAUAUAGAUAGUGAUAUAUUUCAUUUUUAAUUUGUCAUUUUUGAUGUAAAAUAUAAUCACUGCUGUGAUAAAUAAACUAUCUAUUGAUCAUUUAUCAUUUUA